AGAGUGAAACUCACCCAGCUUUAGUAACCAACUCGAUUGCAUAGACUUUAGAUAACCAUGUGAAGGGGAUUCUACCAUCAGAAAAGAGGCCAAACUUCUAUCAUCAUGGUGGAUGUGAAGUGUCUGAGUGACUGUAAAUUGCAGAACCAACUUGAGAAGCUUGGAUUUUCACCUGGCCCAAUACUACCUUCCACCAGAAAGUUGUAUGAAAAAAAGUUAGUACAGUUGUUGGUCUCACCUCCCUGUGCACCACCUGUGAUGAAUGGACCCAGAGAGCUGGAUGGAGCGCAGGACAGUGAUGACAGCGAAGAGCUUAAUAUCAUUUUGCAAGGAAAUAUCAUACUCUCAACAGAAAAAAGCAAGAAACUCAAAAAAAACCCAGUUUUUGAAAUUCAAGAGCAGCAGGAGGAAAUAGUGGAACCAAACACUGAUUAUAAUGAUUCCAAGAUGAUAAUAAGGUGGCCUGAGGCUUCCACCACUAAACGCAAAGCUGUAGAUACCUAUUGCUUGGAUUAUAAGCCUUCCAAGGGAAGAAGGUGGGCUGCAAGAGCACCAAGCACCAGAAUCACAUAUGGGACUAUCACCAAAGAGAGAGACUACUGCGCGGAAGACCAGACUAUCGAGAGCUGGAGAGAAGAAGGUUUCCCAGUGGGCUUGAAGCUUGCUGUGCUUGGUAUUUUCAUCAUUGUGGUGUUUGUCUACCUGACUGUGGAAAAUAAGUCGCUGUUUGGUUAAGUAAUUUAGGAGCAAAGCAAUGCUCCAAGCGAGGCCUCCUGCUUCAGGAAAGAACCAAAACACUACCCUGAAGGGCCAGCCUAGCCUGCAGCCCUCCCUUGCAGGGAGCCUUCCCUUGCACUGUGCUGCUCUCACAGAUCGGUGUCUGGGCUCAGCCAGGUGGAAGGAACCUGCCUAACCAGGCACCUGUGUUAAGAGCAUGAUGGUUAGGAAAUCCCCCAAGUCAUGUCAACUCUCAUUAAAGGUGCUUCCAUAUUUGAGCAGGCGUCAAACAAGGAAA